AGUUCACAGUAUCAGCAGGGCAGUCAAAGCACACUUUUUUCUCUCUCUCUUUUUUUUUUUCCCAUCUCAUCCUUAUUCUUUUUGUUAUGAUCUCUAAAAAGUUGGUGAGUUAGGGAGUGAGGAUCUAUUUGAGUAAAUCCAGCAUGUUUCUCAGUCACCACCCAUCAACCUAAUUGGCAUAGGCGGGGCUGUGCUGUCUGCAACACAGCCAGCUCCUCCAGCUGUGCCAUCCAUCAUACUCAGGCACCCUGGAGCGCACAUGCUCUGCUUCCGGUUGAUUUUAAGUUCCCGAUUCCUGAGCAGGCCUUGGGGAGGCAGUCCCAAGGAGUCAGAGUUGUUUGCUGUCGCAUAUCAGACUCCGGUCUGGGUGACUUGGCUGGUCACAGCACAGUGCUCCUGGGCCCAGGGGCUGUGAUCUCCUGUCAUUUGGUUGCCAUUUUCCUGUGAAGAGGGUAGAGAAUAUGCACCCAGUCAGGAAAACAACUCACGAGGCAAAAAAGUACAUCUCGUGGAUGGAGCAGGGCGAAGUGGUUACAAGUACAGACUCUGGAGCCAGACUGCCUGGGUUUGAAUUGUGCGGUUUCAGCCAUUACCACAUUGAGUGACACACAUUUGACAGGGCUUGAGAAAGUCGUCAAAGGCAGAAGCCAGUGGGAAUCAGCUCUUUGUGCUUGUGGACCCUGCACUGCUCUCUGAUUUCUGCCUGGCAGAUUAACCAACGGCAAGAGAGGCUGAUCUGUCUACAUUCUGAGUACUGCCCUUGGCAAGACACCUAGAACAGACCCUGGACCCAAGUCUACCGUACUACCAUACCCCUACUCCAGCCCACCCCAGACAGUAUUCUGGGGUUCACCUGAGGUCAGCAGUGUGAAGAUGACCAGUGCCUUUUUAGCAUGACGACUUUGGACCAUGUGAUUGCCACCCACCAGUCAGAAUGGGUCUCCUUCAAUGAAGAGCCACCCUUUCCUGCCCACUCGCAGGGGGGCACGGAAGAGCACCUCCCAGGACUGUCAUCUUCCCCAGACCAGUCCGAGAGCUCCUCCGGGGAGAACCAUGUGGUGGAUGGAGGCUCUCAAGACCAUUCCCACUCGGAGCAGGAUGACUCCUCUGAAAAGAUGGGCCUCAUCUCUGAAGCAGCUUCCCCACCUGGGAGCCCUGAGCAGCCCCCACCUGACCUGGCCUCGGCCAUCAGCAACUGGGUUCAGUUUGAAGAUGACACACCCUGGGCCAGCACAUCUCCACCUCAUCAGGAAACAGCUGAGACAGCCCUACCAUUGACCAUGCCCUGCUGGACAUGCCCUUCCUUUGACUCCCUGGGGAGAUGCCCUCUGACUUCUGAGAGCAGCUGGACCACCCAUUCUGAAGACACCAGCAGUCCUAGCUUUGGAUGUUCGUAUACAGAUCUGCAGCUCAUCAAUGCUGAGGAGCAGACGAGUGGCCAGGCUUCUGGGGCUGACUCAACUGACAAGAGGACGGAGUGGCAGACAGGCAGGCAGACGGCAGUGAGUCCUGUUCAAGCAUGCUCGGAGCAUACCUCCACCCGCACCCACCGCCUGGACCCCUCGCCACCCUCACCCCAGCCCAAGAGGAGCCAGAACCCCGGCGAGGGUCCGGAGGGGGCCUCUGCUCCCAAUGACAAUUCCUCCUCGCUUCAAGAAGAUGAAGAAGUAGAGAUGGAGGCCAUCAGCUGGCAGGCCAGCAGUCCAGCCAUGAAUGGGCACCCUGCCCCUCCAGUGACCUCUGCUCGUUUUCCCAGCUGGGUCACCUUUGAUGACAAUGAAGUCAGCUGCCCUUUACCACCAGUCACCUCUCCUCUGAAGCCAAAUACACCACCAAGUGCAUCUGUGAUCCCAGAUGUACCUUAUAAUUCAAUGGGAUCAUUUAAGAAGAGGGACCGUCCCAAGAGCACUUUGAUGAACUUCUCCAAAGUUCAGAAGCUGGAUAUUUCCUCUUUAAACCGCACGCCUUCUGUAACUGAGGCUUCACCUUGGAGGGCAACCAACCCUUUCCUGAAUGAGACUCUGCAGGAUGUACAGCCCUCCCCUAUCAACCCUUUCAGUGCUUUCUUUGAGGAGCAGGAGAGGCGCUCCCAAAACAGUUCCAUUUCCAGUACCACGGGCAAAAGCCAAAGAGAUUCCCUCAUUGUCAUCUACCAGGAUGCCAUCAGUUUUGAUGAUUCAAGCAAAACCCAGUCACACUCUGAUGCUGUUGAAAAACUCAAACAACUCCAAAUUGAUGACCCUGAUCACUUUGGCAGUGCAACUCUACCUGAUGAUGACCCAGUAGCCUGGAUUGAACUAGAUGCUCACCCGCCUGGAUCAGCACGGUCCCAGCCUCGUGACGGGUGGCCAAUGAUGUUGAGGAUCCCUGAGAAGAAAAACAUCAUGUCCUCCAGGCACUGGGGACCGAUCUUCGUCAAACUGACAGACACUGGUUACCUGCAGCUGUAUUAUGAGCAGGGCCUAGAAAAACCAUUCCGUGAGUUCAAGCUGGAGAUCUGUCAUGAGAUUUCAGAACCCCGGCUUCAAAACUAUGAUGAGAAUGGCAGAAUCCACAGCUUGCGGAUAGACCGUGUCACCUAUAAAGAGAAGAAGAAAUACCAGCCCAAACCUGCUGUGGCCCACACAGCAGAGAGGGAACAGGUGAUUAAGCUGGGCACCACCAAUUACGAUGACUUCCUGAGUUUCAUCCAUGCAGUUCAGGACCGUCUCAUGGAUCUGCCAGUGUUGUCAAUGGACUUGAGCACAGUUGGCCUCAACUACCUUGAAGAGGAGAUUACAGUGGAUGUCAGAGAUGAAUUCUCUGGCAUUGUGAGCAAAGGAGACAACCAGAUUCUCCAGCACCAUGUCUUGACACGGAUCCACAUCCUGAGUUUCCUGUCUGGGCUCGCAGAGUGCCGCCUGGGCCUCAAUGACAUCCUCGUCAAAGGGAAUGAAAUAGUUUUGAGGCAGGACAUCAUGCCCACCACCACCACAAAGUGGAUCAAGCUCCAUGAGUGCCGUUUCCAUGGGUGUGUGGAUGAGGAUGUUUUCCACAACUCACGGGUCAUUCUGUUCAACCCUUUGGAUGCGUGCCGGUUUGAGCUAAUGCGGUUCAGGACAGUGUUUGCUGAGAAGACCUUGCCUUUCACACUCAGGACGGCCACAAGUGUCAAUGGGGCAGAGGUGGAGGUGCAGAGCUGGCUGAGGAUGUCAACUGGCUUCUCCGCCAAUCGUGACCCCCUCACUCAGGUUCCCUGUGAGAAUGUGAUGAUCCGUUACCCUGUGCCCAGUGAGUGGGUGAAAAACUUCCGCAGGGAAAGUGUCCUGGGGGAAAAGUCUUUGAAAGCCAAAGUGAACCGGGGGGCAAGUUUUGGCUCCACUAGUGUUUCUGGCUCUGAGCCUGUCAUGAGAGUAACUCUGGGAACUGCCAAGUACGAGCAUGCCUUCAACUCCAUUGUGUGGAGGAUAAACCGACUGCCGGACAAAAACUCAGCUUCCGGUCACCCACACUGUUUCUUUUGCCACCUUGAACUCGGCUCUGACCGGGAAGUGCCUUCCAGAUUUGCCAAUCACGUGAAUGUCGAGUUCAGCAUGCCCACAACUUCUGCCUCCAAAGCCAGCGUGAGAUCUAUCUCUGUAGAAGACAAGACUGACGUCAGGAAGUGGGUCAAUUAUUCUGCACACUACAGCUACCAGGUGGAAAUUGAGCAAAAAAAGAGUUUGAAGCCGGACUUUGAAGGAGAUGAAAUGGAAAAUCCCAAGGAGUGUGGAGUGCAGUGACAAAGCCUUGCGGCAAGGAAUCCUGAUCCCAGAGUCAUGAUAGGGUGUCUUCCUGAGUCAUGAUAGGGUGUCUUCCUGAGUAGCUGAAGUUGCAGUCAAUACCUGCUGUGGCCACUGCAUGUUGGGAACAGUAUACCAGAUCUUCCUGUUUGCAGUUACUUGUAUUUUACCAGGAAACCCUGAGAAUGGUGGCUUUUGGAGAGGCUCUUUGAUUCUGGUCAUGCCUAAAGCACGAGGUUCACCUGACUGUUGGAGCUUACUGUAUAAUUAAGCCUCCUUGUCUUGUCUCUGCUUAUCUCACAGCACUGGUAUGUGGUUUGUUGUGACUGUUACAGUCAGGAAAAGAACCUCCCACAUCAGUGUUAGCACGAUUGCCUUCUGAUGUUCAUCUGUCACUCGCAUAACUUUCUGGCAAAGGCAGUCUUGAGAAGUUAAUUAAGAAUCCAUCUCUUUCACUCUGUCUAGAAAAGGUUCAGAAAAGGUGCAAAACAAAUUUCCUCUUUGGGUCUUACUAGACCUUUUUGAGGUGUCUCCAUUCUUUAACUGUUAAGCUUUCAAGACAUUUCCCUCCUGGCUCUAGAUCGUUUAGAUUGGAACACUUUUUCCAUCUCUCUAAGGUUUCAGUCACAGGAUUUGCUAUCCUGAGUCACAAUAGACAAUGGAAAAAGGCACAAUAGGAGACUUUUUAAUUUUGUGAAUGGACCCACAUUCUGCAAAAUGGGUGUUGAGGGGAAGGCAAAAUUAAUCUUAGUUUUCUUCAUUUUGGAGAAAAGAGACAUUAAAUAUAAGAUGAUGUUCAGUUCAAGAGGUAGAUUCAAUCUCAGUGAAUUCCCAAAUUCACACUGAAAAAUACAGUCCACUUCUGAUUCCUGAAACAAAUAUACAUAAUACCUGAGGCAUUUGUAAGGGGCAUUUGGGAGUUCUUUUUAUACCUCAUGACCAAUAGACAGUUGCAUGUCCCUUUAACCCAACUUUAUAGGAAAUUUAAGCUGCAAAGAUAAUUUUUAAAGCUGUUUUAAAAUUAAGCUUGAAUGAGCUUUCCCCCAAAAUUCAGAGUUUGAUAAUCACAGUAUUGGAUUGGAUUGAAAAGGCAUCUCUAGGGUAGAGACGUGGAAAAGCCAUAUUUUUCUAAUGUUGGGAACAUUAUAUUCUGAUUCCAAGAGUCAGAACGCUCACUCCAUCUUCUUUUUCUUCAUCUGUUUCUGGGACAAUUAAUCUUCUUUUCCUUCAUCCGUUCCUACUCACCUCUGCUUCUUAUUUGUAUCUUAGUGUUUUCUCCCAUGAAGAAUACAAGUCGGGGGACAGAAAGCACACUUCAUUGGAUUUGUAGAUGAUGCAGAAAUGAAAAAUAUCUCCAGUUUUUGGCUGAUGGAUUCAAGAUUAAUGUAUUCAAUGAACAAUCAUUGGAGUCUAAAUGUGUAUUGACACUGGGAUAUAGAAAUAGUUACAGUAUUUUGAAAUAUCUGAACUAAGACUGAAAGUAAAAUGAUGAUUGAAUAGGCAUUAAUGAGAAACCCUAUAUUCUGGGUUUUUAAAAUGCAACCCUCUAAGUACAGAGUGGAGUGUGUGUUUGUGGAUGUGUGUGUUUGUGUGUGUUUAUGUGUGUGGUGUUGAUGGGAACGGUGUUAGGAAGACCUGGUUUCACGGUAGUUUAUAGAGAAAUAUUUCCUUACAGAAAUGGAGGUUCAAUGUUGAAUCAGAAAUAUAUCAUGGCUAUUCACAAAGCUAAUGUAGUCAGCUGGUGUUAAUAAAAGCCUUACAUGCUUUUAUUAACCCUCCAUCUAGUCCAUAUCUAAAUGGAGGGUUGAGUUCAAUUAUGGGUAUCAUAUUUUAAGAGAGACAUUAAUAAGUUGAUUGUGUCCAUAGGGAGGUGACCAGGGUUGUAAAGGGUCUGAUGAUGCAAGAACAAGGGAGUAGCUUCCCUGAAGGAACAGAAGGUAUAGCUGGAAAGGGAGUGCAGACAAGGAGGGAAUGAUACAAUAGCUGCCUAGAAAUUUCUAUUGAGCUAUGAAAAGGAAGAGGAAUUAGAUUUAUUCUGUGUAGCUUCAAAGGGCAAAAAUAAGAACAAAGAGGAACUUUACAGGUGACAAAUGUUUGCUUCAAUAUAAGGAAGAAUUGUCUAAUAAGAGUUGUUCUAAAGAGGAAUAGACUCAAGUUAGUAAGAUUUCCUGUUCCUGUGAAUGCCCAACAGUUAAAAUAACCACCUAUCCCACGUGCUGUGAAAGGGAAUCUUACAUUGGAUUUGGUCUAUAUGUCUACCAAGAUUCCUUCUAAAUAUAGGUUUAGUCUCAAUAGUAAUAAGACUCUCUAACUUCAUUUGUCUUUUUCUUCAUAAGUGGUUUUUCAUGCUCUUUGAAAUACAGUGGAGUUCCUUUGAGGUUUUUGUCAAGGAAUUUCAACGCAUAUCUCUUCCCCUGUUGUACUGAAGGCUUUUGAGAUUAAUUCCUCAUAGAACAUCUAAAUGGAUUGGAGAGUUGGCAAGGGAAAUGAAGCUCAUCCCAGCACCUUCCUUAGUCACUCACGCUUAGCACUCUGUCAAGAUCUCUGCCUCAUCUGCUAGCAUAACAUGUGGAUUGCUUGUUGGAGCUUAUUUCCCCGCCCCCCAUGGUAAAUUCUCAUUUCCUGUGUACAUGCACCUGGACUUUUUUGUUUUUUUUACCAAGAGUUGGGAAAAAUCCCUUCUAUGCUAUCUAUAUUCUGCAAACAAAUUAUUAUUAUUAUUAUUAUUGAGACAGAGUAUUAUUAUUAUUAUUAUUAUUAUUAUUACUGAGACAAAGUUUCGCUCUUGUCGCCCAGGCUGGAGUGCAAUGGCGUGAUCUCGGCUCAUUGCAACCUCUGCCUCCCAAAUCUCCUGCCUCAGCCUCCUGAGUAGCUGGGAUUACAGGCGCCUGCCACCAUGCACCACUAAUUUAUGUAUUUUUAGUAGAGAUGGGGUUUCACCAUGUUGGCCAGGCUGGUCUCGAAUGUCUGACCUCAGGUGAUAAGCCUGCCUCAGUCUCCCAAAGCUCUGGGAUUACAGGCGUGAGCCACCAUGCUGGACCCACAAAUUAUUAUUAAUUUUUAAAAACCUAACAUCUUAAUUUCAUCAAAUUUGUUUUCCCUCUACUGUUUUUAGGAAACUGAUUAUGGGUAGCAUUUAGGGGUUUGGGGAUAAUAAUACUAUAUAUUUUUAGACGUAAUGAGUGUUUUACUAGGUUUAAAUAACUUCUAAAGAAAAUACAAGUGGGCAAAUUAGCUAUGUAAUAACCUACAUAGAAAACAGUUGGGCAAAUUACCUGUGGAUAUGCAGAUUCUACUUUUGCAACCCUGGACCUGGACUUUUUAUUUUUUUUUUUUGUGGUCACAAAUAAUCUUUGUUAUCAAUAAUGUGAAAAUAUUAAAAAUGAAUUCAUUUUACCAGUACAUAGUAUUACUCUUAGAACAUAAAUUAGAUAUCACGUGGUAUCAAGAGCUGUGCUUUCUUUUGAGUCUAGGGCCUGCUUUUUGACUUUACAGCAAAAAGAUAAGAAAUGUACUCAUGACAUGUCAGACAAGACAAUGUGAGGCACUUUGUGGGGAGACCAUUAGAUGAUCCCCCUUGCCUGCUCUUGCAGACAUAGUACUAGUUAUUCCUUAUCAAAAGUUUGCAUUUCAUUCAUAUUAAAUAUUAUCUGGACAGUUUCAUUUUUUCUAUUUGGCUCUUCCCUUACUGUGCCUUCCUGCAUUAUUGGCAGGGUUCAUAAUCCUUGAGAACAUUGUUUGAUUUAAAAUAUUUUUUAUUUGAAAUGAGACUGAUUUCUAUUCAAAUCCAGUGGCUGGGAGUAAGAGUUUAUUUCCCUAGAAACUUAUGUUUCUGAUAAAUGGGAUCCAUGAAGGCAAGGACUAUAUAUAAUUUUUUGUGUUUCCAACACCUAGCACAAAGCUUGGAAUAUAAUAGGGUUCAGCCACCUUAAAUGCUUGCCAGGAGGGCAAACGUAUACUCAUGAAAUAAAGGAAAAUGAGUAUGUAUUCAAUAAAUGUUUGCUGAAAGAAUACUGACCCUGAGACUCGAAGGCUACUUAACCCUUACUUAUCAUCAAAUACUCAUAAUAAAGCCAGCAAGCAUGCUUUUAUUUCCUGAAGGACUUAAAUAAUUUUGCUUUCCUUUUACUCCUGCCUCCAGAGUCAAGUAAUAAAACCUGUCAGCAUUUAGGCACUUAAUAUGCUGCUGAAUUUGAACUACAAUGUACCUCAUUCACAUUGAAAAACAUUUUUGUGCCCCAAAGCAUAGUAGCAUAGAUGCUGUCCAUAGUCACGGUGAUUGAUUGCUUUGUUCCUGCAAGUCAAACAGAUCCAUGAGCCUGAGCCUUGCCCAUUUCAAUGGUCAGUAGGAAAAGAAAGCAUUUGAUAGAGUGCACAACCAGUCUUCAUGCAGUAGGUCUUUGUUCUUCCAGCACUAACCGCUGACCGUUACUUUGCAUUUAUUUUGUCACCACAGUAAGAUGGAGGUCUGAGAUAGUAAGGUCAAAAUUUGUGAGAUAAAGUCAUGAUUUCAGAGGUGAUAUAUAUUUCACCAUAAGUUUAGUGGUGGGAAAACAGAAUGAGCUGAAGUUUUUUCUUAAAAGCCUUGGGAAUAUUAAAUUGGUUUAAGUAGGAAGCACUACCAUCCAGCCUGCUUAUAGAAAUGCUCCCAGUUCGAGUGGUAACUUUAACUCUUCUAAAAAUGAGGAUUAUAUGUUAAUUCCAGCAUAUCUAGACCUUAGUCAGGGAGGUCCAAUCUUUUGGCUUCCCUGGGCCACAUAGGAAGAAGAAUUGUCUUGGGUCACACAUAAAAUACAGUAACAACAGCUGAUGAGCUUUAAAAACAUGGCCAAAAAAUAGCAUUUUCUUUUUUGUUUUUUUUUUUUUUUUUUUUUUUGAGACGGAGUCUCAGUCUGUCACCCAGGCUAGAGUGCAGUGGCACGACAUCGGCUCACUGCAACCUCCGCCUCCCGGGUUCAAGUGAUUCUCCUGCCUCAACCUCCCGAGUAGCUGGGACUACAGGCAUGUGCCACCACGCCUGACUAAUUUUUGUAUUUUUAGUAGAGAUGGGAUUUCAUUAUGUUGGCCAGCUGGUCUUGAACUUCUGAGCUCAGGUGAUCCACCCGCCUUAGCCUCCCAGAGUGCUAGGAUAACAGGCAUGAGCCGCCGCGCCUGGCCAAAAUAGCAUAAUGUUUUAAGAAAGUUUACGAAUUUGUCUUGGGCCACAUUCAAAACCAUCAUGGGCCAAGGGUUGGACAAGCUAGCCUUAGGUCAUGUCCAGAAUGCAAUUUAACAGGAAUUUCAAGCAAAACUAACAAAAAAUUAAAUCCACAAAAAAAUAUCAUUUGGUAAAUGCACUGUCUCACACACUUUACUACUAAGUCCCAUUCAAACCAUGACGACCCUUUACAUAAAAUUAGGGCAUUCUCACCAAGUUUCUAAAGAUGAUUUCUAAACAUUACCAAGGUCUAAGUGCUAAUUCCCCACAAACCAUUUCUUAUCUUGUUUAAAUGAGACUGGCUUUAGAUAUCAUGACUCAUAUUUAUGUGUUUAAGGAAUUAAACGUGAAGGAGAUGUAUAAGGCAACCACAAAUGUAGAAAACAAAUGUAUGUAUUAGUAAUAUUCUCCCAUGUAUUAACUAGAACAAGAAUGUGAGAUUUUUACAUUUCUUCUAGUGUGCCUUAGCAAAUCUGCUGGAAAGAGUCUAGUUGUUUUGAGAAUUGAAAAAAAAAUGUGUCUCUCAAUUUGUCAAUUCUAAGCCUGUAAAGGCAGAAACUAUCCACAGUAAUGAGUUUGGUAGUGCCUGGAGAGAGGCAAAUGAUCAUUGGAUGUAACAAAAGCUACAAGAGAAUAGACUAAAAAAAGAAUUUCAAUAUGAAAAAGUAAAAUCUAGAGAGAUGACAAAUCAGCAUUGGGUACCAAGCCUCAAAAUACUUGAACUAGAAGCCAUCUCUUAAAGUUAAAAGUAAGAAGCUCCAGGAAAAAUAAAGAUUGCAUAGUAAAAAGGGAUAGAUGGCAGGAUUAAUUCAACUCAACAAAUAUUUAUCAAAUGUCUACUCUGGUCAGGUGCUGUGUUAGCAGCCAGCUUCCCUAAAGGGAGGAAAGGCUAGACACGAGGACAUUGAGGAUUGUUUAUUUAAAGUCACUCAUAGGCAUGCCAUAAUGGAUUUAUUAAGGGGAAAUUGGGGUUUCUGUGAAUCUUUACAGGACAUAGCCAUGGAGACAAUCACUAUGUUAAGUAAGUUGCUGUUUUCCCAAUUGGGCUUCAGUUUCCUGAGACAAAAAAGUGAGGAAGUUGGAUUAAUUGUUUCUUCAAGUCCUUUCCAGCUCUAAAGUUGUGGGUUAUUUUACAAAAUAUCCAUUGGUGCCACCUUUCAGUGACUCUUCCUAUGUUUAUAAGAACCAAGAAAUUUAAAUUUUGAAGAUUGGAAAAAUCACCUGGUCCAUCUUUUUCCUUUUCACAUCUCUCUCUUUUUUUUUUUUUUUUUUAUCAUUUCCCCAGACAACAGAAACAGACAACCUUCCAAAUCCUCUAUAUUGCAGUUGCCUUCCACACACAGAUUUAAAAAGAGGAUCAAAGAGGGUGGUGAAGAUCAGGUGGAAUGCUUCUUUGGAAGUUCCACUGGCAUCAUCUAUCAGAACAAUGGUGUGAGCAUGAAGAGGCACAGACAGGUCUCCAAAAUAGAUGUUAGGAUUUGGGUGCUACCUGACACAGAAGUAGGUCUAACCCUCCAAGUACUGGGGAUGAUAGGAUAAUCAAUGAGGUAUAUAUAUAUUUGUCAUUUUGUAUAAAAUAUUGUGAAAAUUGAAGGAGGACACUCAGUAAACAUCCUGGGACUAUUUGUAAGUUAUGGCAAAACCAGAUGAGAGAAAAGGGACAGUCCCCUCUGUAUCCUCGUUGUCUCUUAGUAACAUCAAAUUGUAGUUAAAAAAAUUUUAAACUAUGUACAAGCUACAAAAUAGCAUCUCUUUCAUGGUAUGUUUGAGUGUGUAAUUUUAGUUUCUUUUCUGGUUGUAUUUGUGGUAGUCAGAUGUGUUGGAUUGAUUCCAACUGGACAGAGUAAGGAAUUCCAGCAUCCUCUUCCUGCUUGCUCGUGUUACCCCACAGAUCAAACCCUCAAUUCUAGUUGGGGAUGCUGUCUAGCCCCACACCAUGACUGAAGCCUUAAGCACUGUUGCGCCUCCAUGUGCUUUGGAUCAGCAACCCCAGUGGUAUUCUACCAGAGCAUUGUGGGAAAGCAGAUGUAUAGUCAGGUCCCAACAGCAAAUUGUUGGGUGUGAGAGUUCUAAAGUAUAGGGGUGAGGGAAGAGAAGGAUAUGAACUCCUCUGACCUUAAGCCAGCAUUCAUUUAACUUUUAUGUCUACUUAACAAGAGAACCUGGAGAAAACUACCGUAUUCAAGAGAUUAAUCAAAAUCAGUGUUUUAGCCAGGCGAUGACAGAGAAGCACCAUUCCUCACCCUCCAUUCUUGUAAUGUCUGUAAUAAAUUUCAGUGCGUCAGGAUGGAUGAACCCAAGAUCCAGUGAAUGAUUCAGCUGUUCCAAGCCUUACAUUUUCCAUCAUUCAUCAUCCAUUCUCAUUCAGUGUAACCUCUUGCACUAUUGUGGUUAAUUUUAUGUAAAACCAGUUUAUGUUUUUUUUUUUUUAAUAUGUGCCUAUGUAAUAAAGUCUACACACUGGCUAUCUCUGUAGAGGUGAGGUUUUGUUUUUAGUUGUUCUACUGAUUAUAUCCUUUUCUGAGCUAUGAAAAUGAAUUAUUAAUAAAAAAUUUUUGAACAAAA